GGACUGCAGGGGUCUCAGCGCACCCGGUCGCUGGUGGUGUUUCCGGGAUCCUGGCCUCGUGUGGCCGCCGGGACCUCUCUUCUCAGCCCCAGUCUGCAGUCUGGAGGCCUGGAUGGGACCACUGUCCCCCUGGGCAGGGGCGCGGCGGGGGGCGCUGGGGUCCCAGUUCCUCUGGAGCAGUUGAGUUUGUGAUUCUUGGUGGGAGCUGCCAAGGGAAACAGGGUCGGGCACUGCUCCCAUCUCAGAGAGGAAACUAUUGAGCAGGCCCGCAGAGAGAGGCGGCCUGGAAUCUCCCUCCUUUCUCGUUUCCCCAACACCUGGCGGGCCGUGUAGGGCAGAGGUGUGGUCAGCCUCUUUGCAGGUGGGAAAGCAGAGAGGUUCCGAGCCACGCUGAAACUUGAUCUCUGCAGCCCAAGGGGAGCACUCCUUUGGAAUUUGAACACCUCUGGUAUCUCCUGGCCAGAGAGGGUCAGAGGCCAAGGAGGUGGGGAGGUAGUCCCCUAAUGCGCUGGGAUCGUCCCUCUGCACAGCGUCGUUCCCACUGGAGUCUGUUGUGAGCUGAGAUGACUCUCUGACUUCGGCCUGCGUCCCUGCACACGUCAGCCCUCCGGGCUGCCAAAACACAGGCCAGGCAGCCCUGGGUGAACUAGGGGACCUGCCCAACCCAGCCCACCCCGAGGAAGGAAGGGGGAUUGGCCAGUGUGGCCUGGAGGGUGGGACAGCCCAGCCAAGCUGACGGACCUGCUCGGGAUGGGGUGGGCAUCAGGCAUUUGGAGCGCAGGCAACACCCGCUGGACUCUGACUUCUGGAGUUCUGAUUUGGUCUCUGGUUGAGUGCAGCUUUCCACAGCUCAUGGUUAUUUUGGAGCCGAGCUUCCUGAUCACUCAGCAGGGACCUUGGGCAGUGACUUUGAUGUGGUGGAAGUACCUUCCCCAAGGGGGCUUUUGUGAGGAUUAAGUGAAAUAAUGAACGUAAUAUGCUUAACUUUGUGCCUGGUGAGCUCUAAGUGCUCAGUCGGCGGCACUUCCAGUUUUGUUUUGCUUUGUUUUUCAUUACCGGUCUCUUCCCGGAGGAGGGCCUUCCAGGAAUCACAGGGCUGGACAGAGCCCAGGGGCGGCCCCUCUGGAGGGAGAGGAGGCUUGGCGCCUGAUGCUGCAGUCUCAAUGCACAUGGAGAAAACCUCACAUCCUCACGCUGGCCUGGGAGCCUGCAGGAUGUCUCCUGCCGGCACUGCAACCUCAUCUGUCCUCCUUGCCCCAUCGCUCCUUCCUCCGCAGCCUGACUUCACCCAUUCCACCUUGAGCUGCUCCCCAGGACCGGAGCUCUGCCCCUAGAUCUUUGCACAGCUGACUUCAGGCUGGACCGCCAGCUGGAGACGAUGGUGGACCACUUGGCCAACACGGAGAUCAACAGCCAGCGCAUCGCGGCAGUGGAGAGCUGCUUCGGGGCCUCGGGGCAGCCGCUGGCGCUGCCAGGCCGAGUGCUGCUGGGCGAGGGCGUGCUGACCAAAGAGUGCCGCAAGAAGGCCAAGCCGCGCAUCUUCUUCCUCUUUAACGACAUCCUGGUGUAUGGCAGCAUCGUGCUCAACAAGCGCAAGUACCGCAGCCAGCACAUCAUCCCCCUGGAGGAGGUCACACUGGAGCUGUUGCCGGAGACGCUGCAGGCCAAGAACCGCUGGAUGAUCAAGACGGCCAAGAAGUCCUUUGUGGUGUCGGCCGCCUCCGCUACGGAGCGCCAGGAAUGGAUUAGCCACAUCGAGGAGUGCGUGCGGCGGCAACUGAGGGCCACGGGCCGCCCGCCCAGCACGGAGCACGCGGCACCCUGGAUCCCCGACAAGGCCACGGACAUCUGCAUGCGCUGCACGCAGACGCGCUUCUCUGCCCUCACGAGGCGCCACCACUGCCGCAAGUGCGGCUUCGUGGUCUGCGCUGAGUGCUCGCGCCAGCGCUUCCUGCUCCCGCGCCUGUCCCCCAAGCCCGUGCGCGUCUGCAGCCUCUGCUACCGCGAACUGGCCGCCCAGCAGCGGCAGGAGGAGGCGGAGGAGCAGGGCGCGGGGUCCCCAGGGCAGCCAGCCCACCUGGCCCGGCCCAUCUGCGGAGCGUCCAGUGGAGAUGACGAUGACUCCGACGAGGACAAGGAGGGCAGCAGGGACGGCGACUGGCCCAGCAGCGUGGAGUUCUACGCCUCGGGGGUGGCCUGGUCUGCCUUCCACAGCUGACCCCCGGCCUGCAGAACAUCUGUCCCCAAGCCAGCUCCACUGCCCAGGCCCCCAAGAGGGCAGCUCCAGAAGCUGCCCAGGGCUCCGGGACCCCAUCCCAUGGUGGCAGGUGCAGCGGUGGGGAGUGGCUCUUUCUGGACUCCCAGUGCCUUUUUGCUGGACACUGUGUCCUUAUGGCUUCACUGCAGGUAAUGCCUUUCCCUUCAGGAAGCCCCAGAACACCCACAGGUCUUGGUAACAAACGCCACCUUACACUCUGCAGGCUGCAGCGGCAGCUCCAGAUGGCCUCCUGAGCUGGACGACCCCAGGUCUCCAGACAUCUAGGGACCAGAGCAGGUUUGGGAACACAGAGGGAAGACAGGAUGGGAGUGUAGCCACAGAACCCACCUGCACCCUGACAGGCACACCCCACUGAAGAGCCUGAGUCCCAGGAGGCCUCCUGGAAGCCCAGGACUGCCCACCCACCACGCUGGUGCCCACCGCCUGGCCAGCCAAGCCCUGCCGAUCAGACAUGUGGGCUCCCCGAAGCCCAGCCAGAGACUGCCGUGCUGUGGGUGCCACCAGGCCCAGGGACUGCAGCCUGAGCUCCCCGAGGCCCAGGGCAGCCGGGUGAGGACUCUGUCCUGUGUCACCUCUCUCCAGGUGUCCAGCUGUCUCAUGCCUUUUUGUCCUGUCCUCAGCUCUCCGUGUGGUCAGCGAAACCAUUGUUUUCUGUUAGGACUCAGUUGCAAGAACAGAAACCCUGCCCCCACUUAAUAAUAAAAAAGAAAGUUUAUUGAUGGGUGGUUGCAAAACAAA